ACUACUGGCUACUGGCGCUGCAGCCAUGCAGCCCCCGCCCCCGGGCCCGCUGGGCGACUGCCUGCGGGACUGGGAGGAUCUACAGCAGGACUUCCAGAACAUCCAGGAGACCCAUCGGCUCUACCGCCUGAAGCUGGAGGAGCUGACCAAACUUCAGAACAAUUGCACCAGCUCCAUCACGCGGCAGAAGAAGCGGCUCCAGGAGCUGGCCCUCGCCCUGAAGAAAUGCAAACCCUCCCUCCCAGCAGAGGCCGAGGGGGCCGCACAGGAGCUGGAGAACCAGAUGAAAGAGCGCCAAGGCCUCUUCUUUGACAUGGAGGCCUAUUUGCCUAAGAAGAAUGGAUUGUACCUGAGCCUGGUUCUGGGGAACGUCAACGUCACGCUCCUGAGCAAGCAGGCUAAGUUUGCCUACAAGGACGAGUAUGAGAAGUUCAAGCUCUACCUCACCAUCAUCCUCAUCCUCAUCUCCUUCACUUGCCGCUUCCUGCUCAACUCCAGGGUGACAGAUGCUGCCUUCAACUUCCUGCUGGUCUGGUACUACUGCACCCUGACCAUCCGGGAGAGCAUCCUCAUCAACAACGGCUCCCGGUGGGCAGGGCGGGCCCUGAGGGAGGGGAGCAUGGAAUGGGGUGCCAGGACCCUCCGGGAAGCAGGAACAGGCGCUGGGGGUGAUGGUGGCUCUCUGCUCCAGGAUCAAAGGCUGGUGGGUGUUCCAUCACUACGUGUCCACCUUCCUGUCGGGAGUCAUGCUGACGUGGCCCGACGGUCUCAUGUACCAGAAAUUCCGGAACCAAUUCCUCUCCUUUUCCAUGUACCAGAGCUUCGUGCAGUUUCUCCAGUACUACUACCAGAGCGGCUGCCUCUACCGCCUGCGGGCGCUGGGCGAGCGGCACACCAUGGACCUCACUGUGGUUCUGGCAGCUUUUUAACGCGCUGACGUUGUUCAACCUGGCCCAGGACCCUCAGUGCAAGGAGUGGCAGGUGCUUAUGUGCGGCUUUCCCUUCCUCCUCCUUUUCCUCGGCAAUUUCUUCACCACCCUGAGGGUUGUGCACCACAAGUUUCACAGUCAGCGGCACGGGAGCAAGAAGGAUUGAGGCUGGGCCUUCCCCUGCCGGCCCAGAGGGGCUUCUGUCCUGUGUGUUGUGGGAGGGGAUGGGAGGCGCCCCUCGAGUGUGCGUGUAUCAGGGGGUCUCUUCUAUUCUCCCUUGGGUUUUAUGGGCGCUGUGGGCCCUGAAGGAAGACCUGGGCCCAGUGCCCUCAAUAAAGAGAGGCCCAGAGGUGGCCUGAGCGUGUGUGUUCUCCUGGGGGAGGGGAGGGCUGGGUGGCCCCACCACAUGGGUUCCUGGGGUCUGAGUUAGUUAAGUUGAUGCAGGUGGAGGUCCCAGAUCUACUCACACAAUACCAGGCAAAUACAGAAAACAGAACUUUAUUCCAA